ACACUGGCGCGGCUGUGACGCGACGGAGGCGGCGAGAGCGGCAGCCGUGGGCACUUUCCACGGGUGAGGCCUGGAGAACGGGUGGACGUGCAGGCCAGAACCCGGGACCCACCCGGCUGAGCCCCCAGACUCUCCGCUGCCCACGACCCUCGGAGUGGCACCCUCUCCUGGCCGUCUCCUCUCGUGGGUCCCGAAGAACGGGUGCAAAGCCGAGUUCGUCCGCUGUACUGCGCGGGCGCGCGUUUCGUUCUUCGGUUUUGCCACGGUUCUGUGACUCCCUAAAGGUUGAGGGCUACUGAAUUAGAAGAAACGCCGAGCUGGCUUCUGGUGGGCUGCCGGGCGCCGGGCAGCGUGCUUGGACUGGGGAGGGCAGGGCGUGUUUACUCUGAGUAGAGCAACCGCAAGACCUCCUUUAAAAAAUACCAGUUCUGAGCUUCGGCAUUGGAGAGGCCGCCUGUCAUUCAGCCUCUUCGGACCCUCUCUCACUCCCUGUCUUCCGGAGCGUGAGUGAAGCCCGGGUGAGGUGUUUUCCCACACGCCGGGGGCCCGGAGCUGAGAAGGGGCAUGGCCAGCAUCACGCAGCUGUUCGACGACCUGUGUGAGGCCCUCCUGCCGGCUGCCAAGACUCACCUGGGCCAGCGCAGUGUGAACCGGAAGAGGGCAAAGCGGAGCCUCAAGAAGGUGGCCUACAAUGCUCUUUUCACAAAUCUUUUUCAAGAUGAGACUCAACAGCUGCAGCCUGACAUGUCAAAACUACCAGCGAGAAACAAGAUCCUCAUGUUGUCCUUUGACUUGAGAGUGGGUGGCCUGGGCCCCAAGGCCGACCGUUUGGAGGAGCUUGUGGAGGAGCUGGAAGCAGCCCCUUGCUGUCCGCUUUUGGAGGUGGGGUCUGUUUUGGACCUCCUGGUUCAGCUGGCAGGGAGUGGUCCCCCUCAAGUUCUGCCGAGAAAACGAGACUACUUCCUUAACAACAAGCAUGUGGGGAGAAACGUUCCGUACAGCGGCUAUGAUUGCGACGACCUGAGUGUGUUUGAGAUGGACGUUCAGUCUCUGAUCUCCAGAGAAGAGUGUUUGUGUCACAGCAUGAUCCAGGAAACACUUCAGGUUAUGGAGGCUGCUCCAGGCACUGGCCUGCCCACCGUCGGGCUCUUCUCAUUUGGUGACCCUUGUGGUGACAGGUUCGAGAGAGACACCCGGGUCUCGCUCUUCGGGGCCCUUGUGCACAGCCGCACUUAUGACAUGGACGUCCGACUGGGCCUGCCCCCCGUGCCAGACAAUGCGGACCUCUCUGGGCUGGCUAUUAAGGUCCCACCGAGUGUGGAUCAGUGGGAAGACGAAGGAUUCCAGUCAGCGUCCAACUUGACUCCUGAUUCCCAGUCUGAGCCCAGCGUGACCCCAGACGUGGACCUGUGGGAAGCCGCACUUACCUAUGAGGCCAGCAAGCGGAGGUGCUGGGAGCGAGUUGGCUGCCCCCCUGGCCACAGAGAGGAGCCUUACCUGACGGAGGCGGGAAGGGACGCUUUCGACAAGUUCUGCAGGCUCCACCAAGGGGAGCUCCAGCUGCUUGCUGGGGGCGUCCUACAGGCCCCGCAGCCCGUGCUGGUGAAGGAGUGCGAGCUGGUGAAAGACGUGCUGAACGUCUUGAUUGGGGUCGUGUCUGCCACGUUUUCGCUCUGCCAGCCGGCCCAGGCCUUUGUGGUGAAGCGGGGCGUCCACGUGUCAGGAGCGUCUCCCGAGAGCAUCAGCAGCCUGCUCUCGGAAGUGGCCGAGUAUGGGACCUGCUACACGCGCCUGAGUCAUUUCUCUCUGCAGCCCGUCCUGGACUCUUUGUACAGCAAGGGCCUCGUGUUCCAGGCCUUCACCAGUGGCCUGAGGAGGUACCUGCAGUAUUACCGGGCCUGCGUCCUUUCCACUCCGCCCACCCUGAGCCUCCUCACCAUUGGUUUUCUCUUCAAGAAACUUGGCCGGCAGCUCAGGUACCUGGCCGAGCUCUGUGGCGUUGGCGCUGUGCUCCCGGGCACCUGUGGAGGAGGCCCCAGGGCCGCGUUUCCCACCGGCGUGAAGCUGCUGUCCUACCUCUACCAGGAGGCUCUGCACAACUGCAGCAACGAGCACUACCCUGUACUGCUGUCCCUGCUGAAGACCAGCUGCGAGCCCUACACCCGGUUCAUCCACGACUGGGUGUACAGCGGGGUGUUCAGAGACGCUUAUGGCGAGUUCAUGAUUCAGGUGAACCACGAGUACCUCAGCUUCCGAGAUAAGUUGUACUGGACACAUGGCUACGUGCUCAUCUCCAAAGAGGUGGAGGACUGUGUUCCCGUGUUUCUGAAGCACAUUGCCCACGACAUAUACGUCUGCGGAAAGACCAUUAACCUGCUGAAGCUCUGCUGCCCCCGGCAUUACCUCUGUUGGUCCGACGUCCCUGUCCCCCGGAUCUCGGUGAUUUUCUCCCUUGAGGAGUUGAAGGAGAUUGAGAAGGACUGUGCCGUCUACGUUGGGCGCAUGGAGAGGGUGGCCCGCCACAGCUCUGUCAGCAAGGAGGAGAAGGAAUUACGUAUGGAAAUUGCAAAACAAGAAUUAAUCGCUCAUGCCCGGGAAGCAGCAUCCAGGGUCCUGAGUGCACUGAGUGACCGGCAGAUGUCAGAACGGAUGGCCUUGGAUGCCCGGAAGCGUGAGCAGUUUCAGAGGCUGAAAGAACAAUUUGUGAAGGACCAGGAGCGACGCCAGGCGGCCAGGCAGGAGGAGCUGGAUGAUGACUUCAGCUACGCCCGUGAACUCCGAGACAGGGAGAGAAGGCUGAAGUCCCUGGAGGAGGAGCUGGAGAGGAAGGCGAGGCAGGCACUGGUCGACCACUACAGCAAGCUCUCUGCAGAGGCAGCUCGUCGGGAGCAGAAGGCACUGUGGAGAAUCCAGAGGCACCGACUGGAGAGUGCACGGCUUCGUUUUCUCUUAGAAGAUGAGAAACACAUUCAGGAGAUGCUGAAAGCAGUGUCUGAGGCUCACCAGCCCCAGGAGCCGCCAGACGUCCUCUUGAGCGUGCACCCCCAGGUCACGUCUCCGGGCCCUGAGCACCCAGAGGGAGGCCAAGGCUGUGAUUCUGGGUCUGCAGAGCAACACUCGCCUGCCUGGGAUGGCUGGAACAGGCCAGGCCUGCUGACCCCACAGCCCCUUAAGCCUCUAGCAGUGGGGGCUGGUGGCAGGGGGCUGCAGCAGGCGGAGGGGGCCAGACCCUUCUCUGACAGCCUCAGCAUUGGAGACUUCCUACCUGUGGGCCCAGGGGCUGAGCCGUCCGUGCAGACUGGCAUGGUCCCUCUCCUGGAGGUGGCGCUGCAGACCAUUAACUUGGACCUGCCCCCCUCAGCUCCUGGGGAGGCACCCGCAGCAGCCAGCACUCAGCCCUCCAGGCCACAGGAGUACGACUUUAGUACUGUCCUGAGGCCAGCUGUGGCCACCUCACCUGCACCAGGGCCCCUGCAGGCUGCAGAGUGCAGCUUGGGCAGCUCAGGGCUACAGCUGUGGGAGGACAGUUGUGGGAAGAUGGAUGCCUGUGGCUCCGCCUCGCGGGAGACUCUGCUCCCCUCACACCCACCCAGGCGUGCUGCUCUGGAGGAGGGGAGCAGCCAGCCCACAGAGCGGCUCUUUGGGCAGGUGUCAGGGGGUGGUCUUCCCACAGGGGACUACGCUUCUGAAAUAGCUCCCACCCGGCCACGGUGGAACACCCACGGGCACGUGUCUGACGCCAGCAUCAGGGUCGGGGAGAAUGUGUCAGAUGUGGCUCCCACCCAGCCACGGUGGAACACCCACGGACACGUAUCCAAUGCCAGCAUCAGCUUAGGGGAGUCUGUGUCAGAUGUGGCUCCCACUCGGCCACGGUGGAACAUCCAUGGACAUGUGUCCAACGCCAGCAUCAGGGUCGGGGAGAAUGUGUCAGAUGUGGCUCCCACCAGGCCACGGUGGAAUACCCACGGGCACGUGUCCAACGCCAGCAUCAGGGUUGGGGAGAACGUGUCGGACGUGGCUCCCACCCGGCCACGGUGGAACACCCAUGGACACGUGUCCGAUGCCAGCAUCAGCUUGGGGGAGUCUGUGUCAGACAUGGCUCCCGCCCGGCCACGGUGGAACACCCAUGGACACGUGUCUGAUGCCAGCAUCAGCUUGGGGGAGUCUGUGUCAGACAUGGCUCCCACCCGGCCACGGUGGAACACCCACGGACAUGUGUCUGACACCAGCAUCAGGGUUGGGGAGAACGUAUCGGACGUGGCUCCCAUCCGGUCACGGUGCAACACCCAUGGACACGUGUCCGACGCCAGCAUCAGCUUGGGGGAGCCUGUGUCGGAUGUGGUUUCCACCCGGCCACGGUGGAACACCCAUGUACCCAUCCCUCCGCCCCACAUGGUGCUGGGGGCUCUCUCACCAGAAGCUGAGCCCAACACACCCAGGCCCCAACAGAGCCCCCCUGGCCACACGUCCCAGUCAGCGCUCAGCCUGGGAGCACAGAGCACUGUGCUGGACUGUGGGCCACGGCUGCCUGUAGAAGUGGGGCCAUCUCUGUCCUCCCCCAGCUCGGGCUGCGGGGAGGGGAGCAUCAGCGUGGGGGAGAACGUGUCAGACGUGGCUCCCACCCAACCAUGGUGGCCCAACACCCCGGGAGACAGUGUCUCUGAAGAACUAGGCCCUGGGAGGAGCGGGGACACUGAGGACCUCUCUCCAAAUUGGCCUCUCAACUCACAGGAAGACACAGCUGCCCAGAGCAGCCCAGGCCGUGGUGAGGAGGCGGAGGCAUCGGCGGCGGAGGCUCAGGGUGGGGAGCAGGCCUACCUGGCAGGCCUGGCAGGGCAGUACCACUUGGAGCGGUACCCGGACAGUUACGAGUCCAUGUCCGAGCCGCCCAUUGCUCAUCUUUUGCGCCCCGUGCUUCCCCGGGCCUUCGCCUUCCCCGUGGACCCCCAGGUCCAGUCUGCCGCUGAUGAGACUGCUGUGCAGCUGAGCGAGUUGCUGACGCUGCCCGUGCUCAUGAAGCGCUCCAUCACGGCACCGCUGGCCGCCCACAUCUCCUUGGUGAACAAGGCCGCUGUCGACUACUUCUUCGUGGAGCUGCACCUGGAGGCGCACUAUGAGGCACUGCGGCACUUCCUGCUGAUGGAGGACGGCGAGUUCGCCCAGUCCCUCAGCGACCUGCUCUUUGAGAAGCUUGGAGCUGGGCAAACGCCCGGAGAGCUGCUCAACCCGCUGGUGCUGAACUCUGUGCUGAGCAAGGCCCUGCAGUGCAGCCUGCAUGGGGACACCCCGCACGCCUCCAACCUCUCCCUCGCUCUCAAGUACCUGCCCGAGGUGUUUGCCCCCAACGCCCCGGAUGUGCUGAGCUGCCUGGAGCUCAGGUACAAGGUGGACUGGCCUCUCAACAUUGUCAUCACCGAGGGCUGCGUGAGCAAGUACAGCGGCGUCUUCUCCUUCCUGCUGCAGCUGAAGCUCAUGAUGUGGGCGCUCAAGGACGUCUGCUUCCACCUCAAGCGCACAGCCCUGCUGAGCCACAUGGCCGGCUCUGUGCAGUUCCGUCAGCUGCAGCUGUUCAAGCACGAGAUGCAGCAUUUCGUGAAGGUCAUCCAGGGCUACAUCGCCAACCAGAUCCUGCACGUCACCUGGUGCGAGUUCAGGGCCAGGUUGGCCACCGUGGGCGACCUGGAGGAGAUCCAGCGUGCGCACGCAGAGUACCUGCACAAGGCCGUCUUCAGGGGCCUGCUCACGGAGAAGGCGGCGCCCGUCAUGAACGUCAUCCACAGCAUCUUCAGCCUCGUGCUCAAGUUCCGCAGCCAGCUCAUCUCCCAGGCCUGGGGGCCCCCUGGGGGCCCGCGGGGUGCAGAGCACCCCAACUUUGCACUCAUGCAGCAGUCCUACAACACCUUCAAGUACUACUCCCACUUUCUCUUCAAAGUGGUGACCAAGCUGGUGAACCGCGGCUACCAGCCCCACCUGGAGGACUUUCUGCUGCGCAUCAACUUCAACAACUACUACCAGGACGCCUGAGGCUGCUCUGCGGGGGACGUGCACAAUAAAGGUGUUCUCGGA